AGGCACACAGCCACACGCACACACUCACUGGCAUAUGCACAGCACACACACACGUCCACUUACUCCCAUUACACACUCACAUGCACACACAUAUGCACAGGCACACCCAGACACGCCCACUUAUUCCAACACACUCACAUGCACACACAUAUGCACAGGCACACUCAGACACACCCACUUACUCCCAUUACACACUCACAUGCACACUCACAUGCACACACUCAGACACGCCCACUUACUUUCAUUACACACAUGCACACACACAUAUGCACAGGUACACACACACGCCCACCUACUCUCAUUACACACUCACAUAUGCACACACACAUACCCAUUUACUACUCCCGCUAUGCACUCACACCCACAUACAACACACGCAUAUAGACACAUGCAUACACUCACAUGGAUAUACCCACUUACACAUACACAAUCACACAUAUGCACACGCACAUUGCGCACAGUGACUCACAACACACACAUACACAUGUAUAAGCAUUUACUCCCAUAUACAAGCACACACUGCACUUAUAUAUAUAUGCUUACACACUCAUGCAUGCACCGUCACAUACACGUUUAUACUCCCAUACACACACACACGUACAUUCCAUUCACAUCUACACACACAUGCACACACAUAUUGACUAUAGCAUUCAUGUGCACACACACACUCACAUGCAGUCACGCAUCCACACACACACUCAUCCACACUGUUACACACACACAACCGGACCCACUCACAGGCCCAAGGAACUGUGCCCAGAACACACAAAUGCCCACAGAUGUUCUCAUUUGCAGACAGCAGUGCACCCAGGAGACACACUCAGGUGCCCCCUCAUCUCAUGGAGACAGCCCAAAGAUAAAAACAUCCAGUCUCAACCAGAAACACAAACACUGCACACACUUGGGACACACACACACACACACACUGUGCCACUGUGUGUGUGUAUGUGUGUGGACAAAGGCAGAAACACCGUGGUUUAGGGGAAACAGCCUUGGCAAGUCCAGAGGUGUGACUCUGAUCCCAAUGUUGUCCCUCCAUGCUCCGGGGCUCAGUGCAAACCCCCUGGGCCACUGUGGGCCUCUGGGACCGCACAGGUCAGCUGUGAAAUCCCCGCCACGUGGAGAGCCCUGUUAUUCUGCAAGGCUCUGCCCACCGCAGAACGUUUCCGCGGCCUGCCUGUCUUCCGGGCCUUGGCUCUCUCCGCCUCUCUGUCCUUGUGUGUCUCUCCCGUCUCCAUAGUGUUCUCACGCUCUCUCUCCCUUACUCUGCUCUUCCUCUCUGAUUUGAUCCCUUUUGCUCUCUGCCUUUUUCUGACUCAUGCCCGAACCUUGUCUUAUCUUUGUCUCUUUUUUUGGUUGUGUCUUUCUGCCUGUGCCUCCCUCCAUCUCUCUCUCUCUCUCUUUCUGUUCUGUCUUCACUCUUCCAGUUUCCAUUUCUGAGUCUUGCAUACACACACACACACACGUUGCCACACAGCCCCUCGUCCCGUCCCUGGGUGACAAGCUCAGGCGCUGUGGGGUGUAGCGCUCAGCAGCAGGGGAGACAGUGAGCAGGGAGGAGAGGGGGAGGAAGCACGCCUCCCCCAGCCUGGCCCGAGGCACCAGGAACAGGUGCC